GGUCACAAGGCCGCCCCGGGAGAGAGGACGGCUGGUUGUCUCCCUGCCUCCUCUCUGACGCAGGAGGAAAGACGGUCCCCACACCCUUGGGGAGAGGGACUCACAGAAACACACACAAACACUGGAGAAAGGGAGAUACAAAAGCCCGGACACCCGUGCACAUACACACGGAGAAAUACACCCGGUCACCUGGGAACACACGUACACGCCAGCCUUUCCCCCAACCACUCCGGGACACACAUCCACAGACCCCAAACCAAAUCCUACACCCGAAUGAUUAAUGUAGGGAAAACAAAGGCGCUCCCAUGACUUGAUUUUGGCGACCUCUGAAGUUCCACCUAGCAGAACGUGUUUGCUCGAUGUCUUACGACCACUCGGGUGAGGAAUUCGGAAAGUAAAGCCAAUCUUAGAGGCUGCAGGCGUUUUGGGGGCAUUAUCUGAUUCAGACGCUGGCUAACGUUUCACAAUCGCGUUCCCUUUUUUCUUCCAACUUGGUUGAUGUAAGACAUGACCAUAGAAAGAACCUGUCUGUAAAACUGCCAGUGAAGACUUCUUCAUGUAUUCAUUUCACAGACACUCUUGCACUCCUGUAAUGAGCCUGGCACUGUGAUGAAACACUUUUCCCGUGUCGUUUGAGUGCAUCUUCUCAACAACCCUAGGAGGGUUCUUGAAGCUUUUGAGAUUAACAAUGGCAGGAAAAUCAUCACUUUUUAAAGUAAUUCUCCUUGGAGAUGGUGGAGUUGGGAAGAGUUCACUUAUGAACAGAUAUGUAACUAAUAAGUUUGAUACCCAGCUCUUCCAUACAAUAGGUGUGGAAUUUUUAAAUAAAGAUUUGGAAGUGGAUGGACAUUUUGUUACCAUGCAGAUUUGGGACACGGCAGGUCAGGAGCGAUUCCGAAGCCUGAGGACACCAUUUUACAGAGGUUCUGACUGCUGCCUGCUUACUUUUAGUGUCGAUGAUUCACAAAGCUUCCAGAACUUAAGUAACUGGAAGAAAGAAUUCAUAUAUUAUGCAGAUGUGAAAGAGCCUGAGAGCUUUCCUUUUGUGAUUCUGGGUAACAAGAUUGACAUAAGCGAACGGCAGGUGUCUACAGAAGAAGCCCAAGCUUGGUGCAGGGACAACGGCGACUAUCCUUAUUUUGAAACAAGUGCAAAAGAUGCCACAAAUGUGGCAGCAGCCUUUGAGGAAGCGGUUCGAAGAGUUCUUGCUACCGAGGAUAGGUCAGAUCAUUUGAUUCAGACAGACACAGUCAAUCUUCACCGAAAGCCCAAGCCUAGCUCAUCUUGCUGUUGAUUGUUAGAUUGUUGAUGCAUUCUAACCAACUCACACAUAUACACAAAAUCAACAUGGGGAUGGAGAAGAGAAUUAGCGUUUGCAGCAGUGUAUCAUCUACUAAUAAAAUUAAACUAAUGUUGCUGCUUCAUUAGUUGGUGGGAGAAGGGACACAUCCACUCUUGGAGGAAUAUAUUUACUCAAUAAUGGCACCUUACAUUUAUAAAUUGUAACAGUUGUCUAAUAACGUUUCUUUAAUUUAAAUAUGUAAGUUGCAGAGCUAAUAAAUGAAAUGACCAAGACUUUAAUUAUAAUAAAAAUAAGAAACUUGACUAUUCUAGAAGUUAUACUUGGAUUUUUUCCUGGGAAAAUGGAGAACUACUUUUUAUAUGUGUAUGUUUUUAUGCAAUUAGCAUUGUAUUCUUGGUUCAGGGAAAUACUUUCCUAAAGCAAUAAUGUUAGAUAUUAAAGAUUAAAAUCUAAUGUAUUUGCAAUGCAUUGUUAAUUUACUUCUUCAUUCUCUUCAAAAUGAUUUAACCAUUCCUGUUUUCAUUCUACAUACUAGAAUUACUCUCACUAGUAAUUACUCAUCAUUUGUGUGCCAUUCAUGCACCCCCACCCCCAUAAAUCAUGUUCCACAGUCUCAGGCGGAGGGUGGGCCCCCAGUGGUACAAGAGUUGCUUCAUACAGUCUGUAAUACAUCCAGCUAAAUUCAAGUUGUCUAUGAAUGGAAAGCCUUUCCAUAGAUAGAGUUCAGUUUUAAGAAAAAGGCUAACUACUGAACUUGGAGAACAGACAAAUGUGCAUUUGAUAACUGAUGUAAUAAUUACAAUGUACUGUGUGGAAGAUACAAAAUUACAAUUCGAUUAAUGGACUAAAUAUUUUUGUUACUUUCUUGACCCUUGGGGAAAGUUUCUUAAUUGAAGUUAAAACAUUCCUUUAUAACACAAGACACAAGCUGACUUUAUCACUCUCAGAAGAAAUACUAAGAAGGAUUGUACUUUGUGAGAGGGUAAACGAAGACAUCUUUAUUCGGCAAUGUAUUUACUUAGUGUCUUCUCUAUUACUGAACAUUUAGUGAUUUGCUCUCAAGGAGAUUUUUUGUUAGAAAAAGACUUGUUGCAGUGAUCAGACUUGAUAAAGCAAAUUGUGGUCUUUUGUGGAUGAAGUUCA